AGUGACGCUCCGGAGCCGUCGCCAGGGUGGUAAUACCUGGUGCAGAGCUUGAGUCUGGCCAGCGGGUCAGGCUCUUGCUAGAUCAGCACCGGAGGUGGAAGACUGGUACAUUUUACAUACUUUGGGAAAAAAAAACGUUGCUGAAGUUACUAGAAAAGAGACAGUUCUUCUGCUGACAACUCUUCAGGAAAUAAUUUUCUACCUCCUUAGGAUUCGAAGACCAGUUCAUUCUUAGUGUCUUCUGAAAUAAAAUUAGAAUGGAUUGGGAUGAUGAAUAUUCUCAUAAUUCUUUUGACCUACAUUGUUUGUUAAACUCAUUUCCUGGAGACUUGGAGUUUGAGCAGAUCUUCAGUGACAUUGAUGAAAAGAUUGAACAAAAUGCUGCAAGCAUAAAACAUUGCAUUAAAGAGAUACAGUCCGAAAUUAACAAACAAUGUCCAGGUGUGCAGCUGCAAACAACAACUGACUGCUUUGAAUGGCUAACUAACUAUAAUUACAGUACAUCUGAAUCAUCUUUCAUUUCUCAUGGAGACUUGAUAAAAUUUUUCAAAACACUGCAAGAUUUGUUGAAGAAUGAACAAAAUCAAGAAGAAAUGACAUUGGAUUUACUUUGGGACCUCUCCUGCCACAGCAGCGUUUCAUUCCCAUCAACCCUAAGUGGAACAUCUUUCCAUUUCCUCUCUAGGACGUCUCUUCAUUCUGUUGAAGAUAAUUCCUCUAUGGAUGUCAAGUCUAUGUGGGAUGAUAUAAGACUGCAUCUUCGACGCUUCUUAGUGAGCAAAUUACAAAGCCAUAAUGAAAUAAACAAUUCACAGCAAAAAAUUUUAUUGAAAAAGCAGUGCUUACAACAACUCUUGUUUCUUUAUCCAGAAUCAGAAGUUAUAAUCAAAUACCAAAACAUACAGAAUAAACUGUUGGCUAAUCUUCUGUGGAACUGCUUUCCUUCUUACAACAGAGAUUCAAAUUUAGAUGUAAUAGCUCAUGGAUAUCAAAGUACAAUGCUUAAGUUAUACUCAGUAAUAAAAGAGGAUUUUAACACACUAUGUGAAAUUUUAGCUCCAUCUUCAAUGGUGAAAUUCAUUAAAGAAACUUACCUGGAUACUGUUACAGAAGAAAUGGCAAAAUUUCUUGAAAAUUUUUGUGAGCUGCAGUUCAGAGAAAAUGCUGUUCGUGUGGUUAAAACAAGCAAGAGCUCCAGCAAGCAUAGAGGAGCAGUGCAUGCUUUGGUUACUACUGAAUGCCCACAGAAAGGAAGAAACUUCUCUCUCCCUUUAGACAAAGUCGAAUUCUUAUCGCAGCUCAUAAAAUCCUUUAUGAAACUGGAAAAAGGUGUUCAAGAAUUGUUUGACGAAAUACUUUUAUCACUCAAGAUAACCAGGGAUACUUCAGGAAUUUUGGAGAAAUCCGAUAGAGAGGUUGUAAUGGAAAAACCUAGAGCAAACGAAACCAAUAUUCCUUCCGAGCAAUCACUACCAGGAAAAGAGGCUACCUUACUAGAUUUUGGCUGGAGAAGUGCAUUUAAAGAAGUGUCUCUUCCCAUGGCGCACUGCGUAGUAACUGCAAUUGAAGGUUUUUCCACAAAAAUUCUCCAACAGGAACAGAAUGAAAGGUCUUCAGCUGUGAGCUAUGCUAUGAACCUUGUAAAUGUCCAGCAAGUUUGGCAAGACAGCCAUAUGUUUCCUGAGGAGGAACAACCAAAGAAAAUUGGAAAAUUUUGUUCUGACAUCAUGGAAAAACUUGACACAAUGCUUCCACUGGCUCUGGCAUGCAGAGAUGAUUCUUUUCAGGAAAUUAGAGCAAACUUGGUGGAGGCCUGUUGUAAAGUGGCAACAGCUGUCCUGCAGAGACUGCAAGAGAGAGCCAAGGAGGUUCCUUCCAAAGCACCCCUGAAAAACUUGCACACAUACCUCUCCACAGCGGUGUAUGUCUUCCAGCAUUUCAAGCGAUAUGAUAAUUUGAUGAAGGAAAUGACUAAAAAACCCAUAUUCCUGGUGCUUGUCCAACGAUAUCAGGAAUUCAUCAACACUCUACAGUUUCAGGUUACGAACUACUGCGUCAGAGUUUGUGCUACAAGCAUUUUACAGGAUGCUGAGAGCCACCACUGGGAUGACUACAAAGCUUUUUAUGAGGGGGAAAGAUGUUCCUUCUCGAUCCAGAUGUGGCAUUAUUUCUGCUGGUCUCUUCAUUACGAUCUCUGGACCAUUCUGCCUCCUAAGUUAGCCCAGGAGAUUCUAGUGGAAGUGCUGGAGAAAUCUUUGAGUCUACUGGCCUCCAGAUACGCUCGGGCCCACCCCAGCCGUAAAAGAACUCCACAGUUAAGACUUGAUGUCACAACAAUUUUGAUAUGCACUGAGAACAUGUUAUGGUCAGUUUGUACAUCUGUACAGAAACUUUUGAAUCCUCAUCAGCAUACAGAUGAUAAAAUUUUUAAAAUUCACACUCAUUGUAAUAAUCUGUUUACAACAUUAGUCAUUUUGACUUCACCAUUAACAGAAUUAUAUAAGACUUUUCAGCAUGGCCUGGAUGAGUCUGCUUCAGAUUCCUUAAAAUCAUUUUUUAAGCAACCAUUAUAUUGGGUUUCUUGCAUAUCACAUUUCUACCCUUCUUUACUCAGGACUCCAUCAGCUGGAGGACUGAAAGCCGAGGGUCAGUUGAAACUGCUCUUAUCCCAGCCACGUUGUAACUGGAACUUGCUUCUGGAAACCCUACUGCAUCAUGAUGGACUUUUACUGAGAAUCUUGCUGAAGAGCUCAAAACGUACCUUUCAAGAACAAGUUUCCGACACAGAAAAUAACCUGAACCAAGGACCCAGCUUGAUGGAAGCCAUCUUUAAAAUAUUGUACCAUUGCAGUUUUUCUCCACAAACAUUUGCAAACGUUUUUGUGAGCUACAUGGAAGAAGAGCAAUUAUGGGACUUUUUAUAUAACAUCCCAGUCUCAACGUGCGUGGAGUACGAGCUAGAGGUCAUCCGAUGCUUGAGACUGGCACUGACCGAUGCCAUCAAGGACACUGUACAGCAGAUAGUAUCUGUAAUGAGUUCUAGGAGAAACUGUGAGACAAACCUAAACAAGCACAUUGUUCCUGAUUGUUUGCUUGAGAGCAUGCCAAAGGAAUGGAAUUAUAGUCCAAAAGAAACUAACAGGAAAGAAUCAUGCAAAAGCUUCACAAGGCUUACUGCUCAGGCAGUAUCUAUUGUAAUCAGCAAGUUACCUACGGUGAUUGCAUGUUUGCCUCCCCCAGUUAAAUACUUCUUUUUUCUGUCUGAGAGAAAAAUGUCAAAAAAAUUUGUUGAAUUGAAGAAAGCUGGCCUGCUUGUCUGGAACUUGAUUGUAAUUAUAUGUCGGAUAUUUGAGGACGGAAACACUGUGGAACUUUUAACAGGUGCCUCUCUUGACAGAUGGAGUAAAGAAAAAUUGGGUUUAAUUUGUAUGUGUUUGAAAAGCAUCAUGGGAGACCAGACAAGUAUCCAUAAUCAAAUGAUCCAAAAGGUCAUACAGAGCAUUGAGCAGCAGAAGCCCAACUGGAUUGAACGUCAAUUGUUGAAAGCAAGGAAACUGAGCACUGAAUGUGCAUUUAUGACAAUAGAGAAAAGCACGGCCUUACAAGAAGGAGAUGUUGCUCUUGAACUGACUGAGCAGAAAAUAAACACGAUGGUCCUGGAUCUCUGCCACAAACCAGGUGGCAGGGAGUACCUGAGGCAAAUUUAUCACAUCAUGCAGCUCAAUGAGGAAUAUUUAAAAGAACAGCUGUUUUCUAUGAAUAGUUCAGAGGAAAAGCCAUUACCCAUCCGACCUUUAAAGACGACCUUGAGGAGUAUAGAAGAUCAGCCUUCUGCCUUUAACCCUUUCCAUGUGUAUAAGGCGUUUAGUGAAAACAUGCUAGAUCAGUCAGCCAUCACAAAAUGGAACUGGAAUUGGGCAAAGUUGCUGCCAAAUUAUCUGAGACUGGAUAAGAUGACCUUCAGUGUGCUGCUCAAAAACAGGCUUUCCUUCACCAACACAAAGAAACAUCUUUGAGAGACAGAAUACCACACUAAAAUCAUCAGGGACCCAUCCGUGGAUUUAUGCUUAGAAAGAAUGGAAGGUAAAUAUGUAGGUCUAUGAAGACCAUGUUCUUUCUCCUACUGAAUUAAUACAUCUCAGGCCUCUUCCCAGCACUGCGUUAUGCAUUUUUUGGGUGAAUAAUUGAAUGAUUUUAAUUUUGCAAGCUAUAAAAUUUUAUUAUAUUUUACUUUUUCUCCACUACAACCUGACUCCAUCAAGGAGCUCAACUGAUGUUUAUGCUUGAUACUUCAAGUUAGACAGGUAUAGCUUGCUGUGCUUUUUAAAGAGUAGCUAACAUAUGUAUCAUGUAACAUAUGUAUCAUGAGCUUUUUCACAUAAUGUCAGACUAAUUAAUGUAUUAUAUUUCACUGCAACAGGAUCACAUUAGUCUUGAUAACUUAAUCAUUCAGACUGGUCUAUUGUCUUCCACCAUGAACUUAAAAUGAUGUAAGUAUACUUAGAUGCACUGAAUUGUGAAAAAUAUAAAAUACGUAUGAAUAUGAACAUUUUAAAUUGUGAACCAAAAUUUGUCUUCAUUUUGUAUAAAUAACUCAGGUAGGUAACCAUUAAAGUACGGUUCUUCCUCUGUAUCCUUGGAUUCUGUAUCCAAGGAUUCAAUUAACCUCAGAUUGAAAAUAUUCCCCCCCAAAAAAUGGAUGGUUUGUGUCUGUACUAAACAUGUACCGACUUUUUUCAGGUCAUUAUUUCCUAAACAAUACAGCAUAACAACUAUUUUCAUAGCACUUACAUUGUAUUAGGUAUUAUAAGAACUCUAGAGAUGAUUUAAAGUAUAUGGGAAGAUGUGUGUAGAUUAGAGCAUCUGGAGCACCUAUGCAUUUUGGUAUCCAAGAGGAUCCUGGAACCAAUCCCCCAUGGAUAUCAAAAAACAACUGUAUAGGUUAAAAACACAGCAUAUGUUAACUCAACCAAACAUUUUAUUUAUCAUAUCAAGGAGAAUAUGAAUAGUAUUUUUCAGUGCACAUGGGAAAACUUCUAGACACUCUUCAAAAAUGAUUUCUUUUAAGAGGAAUGCUUUCUUUAACCCAUAAUUGAAGAAAGUAAGAUUGGUACUUUUAGAGUUCACUGAUGAAAAUGGGGAUAUAUUUUAGAUUGCUUUUUAAGUUUAUAAGGUAGAUUUAGUAAUUUUAAAUAAAUAUUUGGCCUGUUUCUUAAAGAACAGGACAAGUCUUAUGCUACCAAAUUCAACUACCAUGCUAAAUGAGAUUCAAUACAUGUCCUAAUUGUAUAAGGUUUGUGUUUGGACACAAAAAAUGUGGGCCAAACUGACUGAGUUGAUGUAUAAUUAUAAGUCUACAUGAAAAAUGCAAUUACGAGUAGUUCCAUGGAAUUGGAAACUGUGCUUUCUCACAUUGUCUCCCGAGUGCCUGGUGAGACAUCAGGCUUGGUGGUGGUGGAGAAAUACGUGUUGAAUGAAUGUAUGAGAGGAAGCAUUUAGAAUAAAAAUGCGUUGACGCUACAGGAACUAAGACAUAAGAUAUUCAAUACGGUUCACCACUGAGUUCUAAAAAACAAUGUUUUUCUACUUUGAUUUUUAAAAGAACCACAACUCCCAAGUCAAUGAGAAAAAGCUUCUGUAAAUCAGCCACUAAAGUCUUAUUAAAUCACAAAUACCAAAGAUGUAAAAAUCUAUCUACAAUUUUUAGCAACUCAUCAUACUAAAACUCAUCUGGGAAGAAAAUAUUCAUAGGAAUUAAAGUGCUUUAUUUAUAAGAGGCACAAUUAAGAUGGAUGCUCAUUUUUAGUGAUUAGUAUACUACCCCCUAGUUAAUAGAAUCCUCUAGCUUUCCCCAGAAGAUGAGGGUGAGCUAGUGCAUUUAGAAGAAAAUGGUACCUGUCUACAUCUACGAACAGCUUAUUUUGCAGAGCGGUAUAAAACAAGUUCAAUUUUGGUAUGUAAAAAAGCAUUAUUAAUAUUUUUAAGGAAGAAGAAAGAAAUAUGUGAAAAAAUGAUUACAAAUAUAUGUUAAAUUAUAAGGUUUGAUGUCUUUAUAUAAGGCAAAUGUAACAAUUUGAAUAGUAUUUAUUUAUUUAAUAAUCUGUUAAAAAUUAAUGGGCCAUUAUAGUCUUUAUUAUUGUAAUAGAGAAAAGGACUUUCCUAUUUCAUAUUUGUUCAGUAUGUAAUAAAUCUAUUGGAUUUUUAAAUGUGUUUAUACACAUAUAUAAUCACUCAUUGCUUAUUGCUGAGAAAUGUGUAAUUAGGCAAUUUUGUUUUGCAAACAUCAUAGUGCGUAUCUAUAAACCUAGAUGGUAUAUGCCUAUUAUAUACCUAGGCUAUAUGAUAUAGUCUGUUGCUCCUAGGCUACAAACCUGUACAGCAUGUGUCUGUACUGGAAUACUGUAGGCAAUUGUAACAAAGUGGUAUUUGUGUGUCCAAACAUAACUAAACAGUACAGUAAAGAUAUGUUAUUAUAAUAGAAAAAGUACAGUAAAAAUAUGUUAUUAUAAUCUUACAAGACCAAUGUCUUCUAUGUAGUUCAUUAUUGACUGAAAUACCAUUAUGUGGCACAUGUGGCACCAUAUAUAGUAUACACACACACCCACACAUACACACAUAAAGUAAAUGAAAAGGAGAAAUCAGAGCCUGGCAUUUUAUCCUAUAACCUAAGCAGAGUCAAAACGACUACAUUUUACUUAAAAAAGGAUUCUUUUCCCACAUAAUUAACAUUUAGCUAUCUAUCCUGACUCAAGGAGAUACAGUCAUGAAAAGCCCAAAAUACUGUAGCAUAUAUACUGCAUAAAAAAUACUGUUAGAUUUUCUUAUUGUAACAUUAAACAUAAUUCCUCAAUUCAAUUCAACCUUCAAUGGAGAGAAUUAUCCCAGCUUAAUGGAGAGAAUUAUCACUCAUCUGGUUGAAUAAGCUGGGAACCUGGGUGUUGUACUGAACCAGUCUUUCAUUCAUGCACCCCAUUUCCAAUCCAUCAUAUAUCCAUUUAUUUCUCUCUCUCCAACCAUUCCACUUCUGGUUUCAUUUUCACCACUUUAGUGUAAGGUACCAUCAUCUCCUAUGCAGAUUACUUCAGGAGCUCGUAACUGGCCUCUGUUCUUCUGUCUACCCAGGUCCUAUCCAGUCUCUGCAAGAACAAAUCUAAUUAUGUUAUUCUCUUGCUUUAAAAGUCUUCAAAAGCACUUAGAAUGAAAUCUCAACCUGAAAUCUGGCCUACAACUCCUGCAUGAGCUGCCCUGCCUGUAGCUCCAGUCUGAUUUCAUUCCUCACUCACUGUAGGUAACUUCUUAUGCCCCAGCCUGUCAUGGCCUUCUUUCAGUUCUGGAAAUGGUCUAUUCUCUUUCCCACUUUGGUGCCUGUGUAUGUCCCUGCUCUCUAGACUAUUCCUCAGAUACACCAACCCUCUUCAUUUAAGUUCUCAUCAACUUUAAUAAUAAUUCAAUGCUAAAUUAUAAUCCAUAUAGUAAAGAGUAAAUGUGCUCAUCUCCAGAUUUAAUCAAUAAUUAUAAAUUACAGAACUAACUUGAUAAGCUCUUUAAAAAGUGUCAAAGAAUAAUAAAUGUAAACAAUAGAGAAACGAUAGUAUAUGUAAAUGAAGAAUUAACCUAGGAUUUAUGAGUGGUAGGGUAAGAACAAAGGAAGAAUUAUACACAUUUAUUUGAAUAAAACCAAAUAGCUGAAGAAAGAUCUGAAUGGACAAAUUACAAAAUUCACACAAGUUCCAAGCAAGAAUCAUGAAAUAAGAUCCAUACCAAUACGCUGAAUUCUUAAAACAACUUUACUGUGGUAUAAUUUAUAUACCAUAAAACUUAGCUAUGUGAAUAUACAAUCUCAUUUUUUUUCUAAAUUUAUAGUUUCCAUCACCCCAAAAUGUUUCUUUAUACAAAUCUGCAGUCGAUCCUUGCUCCCACCCUCAGCCCUAAAGAACCACGGAUCUGCUCUGGACAUUUCAUAUAUAAAGAAUCAUAUGAUAUCUAUUUUAUACUUGUACUCUGUGGUAAUGUUUUUGAGGCACAUGUAUCAGUUUAAGUAGUUUCUUGUUAUUGCUGACUAGUAUUCAAUUCUUUUAAAUGUAUUGAUACUUAUUUAAUGGCCUAGCAUAUGAUCCAUAUUGGAGAAUGUUCCAUUUUUGCUUGAAAAGAAUGUGUAUUCUCUGUUGGUGGGAGUGUAAAUUAGUUCCGCCAUUGUGGAAGACAGUGUGGUGAUUCCUCAAAAAUCUAGAACUAGAAAUACCAUUUGGCCCAGCAAUCUCAUUACUGGGUAUAUACCCAAAGGAUUAUAAAUCAUUCUCCUAUAAAGACACAUGAACACGUAUGCUUACUGCGGCACUAUUCACAACAGCAAAGACUUGGAACCAACCCAAAUGUCCAUCAAUGAUAGACUAGAUAAAGAAAAUGUGGCACAUAUACACCAUGGAAUACUAUGCAGCCAUAAAAAAGGAUGAGUUCUUGUCCUUUGCAGGGACAUGGAUGAAGCUGGAAACCAUCAUUCUCAGCAGACUAACACAGGAACGGAAAACCAAACACUGCAUGUUCUCACUCAUAAGUGAGAGUUGAACAAUGAGAACACAUGGACACAAGGAGGGGAACAUUACACACUAGGGCCUGUUUGGGGGGUGGGGGGCUAGGGGAGGGAUAGCAUUAGGAGAAAUAUGUAAUGUAGAUGACGGGUUGAUGGGUGCAGCAAACCACCAUGGCAUGUGUAUAUCUAUGUAACAAAACAUGCACAUUCUGCACAUGUAUCCCAGAACUUAAAGUAUAAAAAAAAAAAAAAGAAAGAAAAGAAUGUGUAUUGUACUAUCAUUGGGUGCUCACUUCUAUAGCUAUUAGUAGAGACAGGGUUUCACCAUGUCGGCUAGGCUGGUCUCAAACUCCUGACCUCAGGUGAUCCACCCGCCUCAGCCUCCCUAAGUGCUCAGAUUACAGGUGUGAGCCACUGUGCCUGGCUGCAAUGAUUUAUGAAACCAGUGUAACCUUGACACUAAAUCCUAAUGAAGAUAAUUCUCCUGGAAACUGUAGACAAUUAUAAAUGAGAAUAUACUAAGCCAUAUAUGAGCAAAUCAAAUUUGACACAACAUUAUGGAACAAUGCAAUGCAAUUAACUUAGCUUUAUCUUAAAAAGUUAGUGAUUAUUUAAAAUAUUAUGGCAGUCUGGCAGGGUCAAAUUAAAAAGCCAUGUGAUAAUUUUAGUAAGUGACUCAAUAAUAUUAAUACACUUCCUGAUAAAAAUUCUUAGUUAUCUAAAACUGAGGUGGAUAUUCCUUUAACUUAAUCUCAACCUAAUCAUUUUCAUCAUAAUCAAUAUGGUAAGAGCUAAUCUUAUUAAAAUGGGAAUAGGAUAAAUGCUUGAUAUAAUCAAUUAUUAUUUCAUAUUAUUAUUUAGGUUUUAACUCUUGUGGUAAGAGAGGAAAUAUGUGUAAGUAGUAUAAUUUGGGGAGAAAAUGAUAUACUAUGAUAAUUAUUUCCAAUAUGAUAUUUUUACAUAUAAAAUUAAUGUGAGAAACAGAAUUAAAGAGAGAUCAGUUAUAAAGCCAGUUUAAAAAUAAUUGUACAAAAUUAAUAUUUUCUUUAUAUGGUGGCAAUACACUGAAAAUAUGAGAAAUAACAGUAACAUCACUAAUCCAAGAUCACUUGGUACACUCUAUGAGAAAUAUACAUAAUCUAUAUUAAGAAAAAUGUAAGAUUAGACUGAAACAAAAGAUAAUAAAUGAAGACAUAUAGCAUGUUCCAAAGUAGGAAAAUUGAAUAUCAUAAAGAUGUUAUUUUUCCAAACUUAAUUUCUAGUUUUACUGCAAUUUCUCUCCAAACCUCUACUGAACUUUGGGGGACAGUAAAGUGAGAAACUUGAUGACUAAUUCUAAAUUCAUAUUGAGGAGUAAAUAACAAUAGCUAUUUUUAUUUUAGAAGAUAAGUAAUGAGGGGGUAAUCGAACAACCAGAUAUUAAACACAUAAAAAAAUCUGCAAUAGUUGAAAGUAUAGAAUUCAUUCAAGAAUUGACAAAUGAACAGAACAAAUCCUGGUUUUAUUCAGUUUAAUAUCUGUGUAAGUCCCUGAGACUUUGAAGUUGUUACAGCAUCAUAAUUUGGUGUAUCAUGAUACACCUUCUGUUUUCUGUGAGAUAGGAUCCUGUAUUUUAAACAGAAUUACAUGCCAAAAUUAAAGCAUGUUGCUCUUCUGAGUUUGAAGAUCUCACCAAAUGGAGAGUGACUUUCCAUUACCAUGAUAAAGCUAGACUUUAAAAAGUAGUUUGUGGCCGGGUGUGGUGACUCACACCUGUAAUCCCAGCAGUUUGGGAGGCUGAGGUGGGCAAAUUGUUUGAGGUCAGGAGUUCAAUACCAACCGGGCCAACAUGGUGAAACCCUGUCUCUACGAAAAAUACAAAAAAUUAGCUGGGCAUGGUGGCCCAUGCCUGUAGUCCUAGCUACUCAGGAGGCUGAGGCAGGAGAAUCACUUGAACCUGGGAGUCGGAGGUUGCAGUGAGCCGAGAUUGCACCACUGCAAUUCAGCCUGAGCAACAGAAUGAGACUUCGUCUCAAAAAAAUAAAAAAAUUAAAAAAAUUAAAAGUCGGUUGUGAAAUCUUUAUUCUACCUUUUUUCUUCUGGGACCAAUAGGAAAUUUGUUUAUUGGAAGGUAACCAGUGUUUAGCAUAACUAUUUGGACUUCUUCUGUUGAACUAUGUGAUAUGUUUUGCAUAGGCAAUCAUAUCAUCUACAAAUAGAUGUUUCAGUUUUUCCUUUACACUAUUUAUGUCUUUCAUAUCUUCUACUUGUCUUACUGCACUGGCUGAGACUUUCUGUAUCGUGUUGAACAGGAGUAGCGAAGGCAGACAACUUUUUUUAUUCCUGAUGUUAAAAAGCAUAGUUUAUGGUCUUUCACCAUUAACUAUUAUCAUUAAUCGUAAUUUUUUUGUAGAUGCACUUUAUCAGGUUAAGAAAGUUCCUUCUAAUUCUGUGAAGAAAGUCAAUGGUAGCUUGAUGGGAACAGCAUUGAAUGUAUAAAUUACUUUGGGCAGUAGGGCCAUUUUCAUGAUAUUGAUUCUUCCUAUCCAUGAGCAUGGAAUGUUUCUCCAUUUGUUUGUGUCCUCUCGUAUUUCCUUGAGCAGUGGUUUGUAGUUUUCCUUGAAGAAGUCCUUCAAAUCCCUUGUUAAGUUGUAUUCCUAGGUAUUUUAUUCUCUUUGUAGCAAUUGUGAAUGGAAGUUCACUCAUGAUUUGGCUCUCUGUGUGUCUGUUAUUGGUGUAGAGGAAUGCUUAUGAUUUUUGCACAUUGAUUUUGUAUCCUGAGACUUUGCUGAAGUUGCUUAUCAGUGUAAGGACCAAAAAAGAUCCUGUAUAGCCAAGACAAUCCUAAGCAAAAAGAACAAAGCUAGAGGCAUCACAUUACCUGACUUCAAACUAUACUACAAGGCUACAGUAACCAAGACAGCAUGGUCCUGGUACCAAAACAGAUGUAUAGACAAAUGGAACAGAACAGAGGCCUCAGAAAUAACACCACACAUCUACAACCAUCUGAUCUUUGACAAACCUGACAAAAACAAGCAAUGGGUUAAGGAUUCCCUAUUUAAUAAAGAUGUUGGGAAAACUGGCUAGCUAUAUGCAAAAAAACCGAUACUGAACCCCUUCCUUAAACCUUAUACAAAAAUUAACUCAAGAUGGAUUAAAGGUUUAAACACAAGACCUAAAACGAGAAAAACCCUAGAAGAAAACCUAGGCAAUACCAUUCAGGACAUAGGCAUGGGCAAAGACUUCAUGACUAAAACAC